ACUGCCUGAGCUGUGGCUGAGCAGCAGAUUGGGGAGAAACAGGCUCUCGCACCUUGGUAAGCUCAGCCACUUUCGGUGAGACCCCCGAGGCUUUGGGAAGCCACCCUUGGGCAGGACAUAAGCAGGACUUAUCUCCCUGCAGCGUCUAGGGCAGCACCGUCCAAUAGAAAUAUGAUGUGAGCCUUACAGUCCUUUAUUCGACGAUUUCUUCAAUGGACAGAAUUAUUAGAUCCUACAAAUGUGUUCAUUUCAGUUGAAAGUAUAGAAAACUCGAGGCAACUAUUGUGCACAAAUGAAGAUGUUUCCAGCCCUGCCUCGGCGGACCAAAGGAUACAAGAAGCUUGGAAGCGGAGUCUUGUAAGUUUCAGCCCCUUCCUAAUUUUUAGUGUCCUAUAAUAACAAAACCAGACAUCCAGCUAACCUUGCAUCUCUCCUUUUGAAGGCAACAGUGCAUCCCGACAGCAGCAACCUGAUCCCCAAGCUUUUUCGACCUGCAGCGUUCCUGCCUUUCAUGGCACCCACGGUAUUUUUGUCAAUGACGCCACUGAAAGGGAUCAAGUCCGUGAUUUUACCUCAGGUUUUCCUCUGUGCCUACAUGGCAGCGUUCAACAGCAUCAAUGGAAACAGAAGUUACACUUGUAAGCCACUAGAAAGAUCAUUACUAAUGGCGGGAGCCGUUGCUUCUUCAACUUUCUUAGGAGUAAUCCCUCAGUUUGUCCAGAUGAAGUAUGGCCUGACUGGCCCUUGGAUUAAAAGACUCUUACCUGUGAUCUUCCUCGUGCAAGCCAGUGGAAUGAAUGUCUACAUGUCCCGAAGUCUUGAAUCCAUUAAGGGGAUUGCGGUCAUGGACAAGGAAGGCAAUGUCCUGGGUCAUUCCAGAAUUGCUGGGACAAAGGCUGUUAGAGAAACGCUAGCAUCCAGAAUAGUGCUGUUUGGGACCUCAGCUCUGAUUCCUGAAGUCUUCACCUACUUUUUUAAAAGGACCCAGUAUUUCAGGAAAAACCCAGGGUCAUUGUGGAUUUUGAAACUGUCUUGUACUGUCCUGGCAAUGGGACUGAUGGUGCCAUUUUCUUUUAGUAUAUUUCCACAGAUUGGACAGAUACAGUACUGUAGUCUUGAAGAGAAAAUUCAGUCUCCAACAGAAGAAACAGAAAUCUUUUAUCACAGAGGGGUGUAGGCGUGAGUUUUAGGUGAAUUUAUGUGGUUCCUGCUUGAAAACCUUCCCCUCUCCAGGUUCGGUUUAGAGAACUUUGCCACAGGUCUUCUGGGGACCCCAGAGGUGUCUGUGCUGACAAGGCGACUUCAGAUUCCAUACUGAGAUCGUUCCCAGGCUGGCGUCUCUGGGGUUUUUAAGGCUGGCUGGAGAAGACAGUGGGAGGGUGCCCCGUCUGACACCCCUGGGGUUGCUGAGGGAACGGUUGGAGUGGGGAUCGGCCUGCGAAAGGAUACUGUGAAAUCACUAAUUAACUAAUAAACCUGUCUCAAGUUGAGGAUUUGAAGAAAGAACACAGAGUCCACCGUGCCCAGGACACAGGUGUUAAAUGGAUAGGCCGUCUCAAGCGGAACACGUACCCCUGGGGCGCUGUUUACGCCCUCCAACCCCAAAAGCAAUCUUGUUUCCUUACUCAGUGUCCUCCAUUCUAGACAGCUAC